GCUCAGCUCCUGCAAUGGGGCCUGCCUGACACUUGGGCGCUCCUUCAGUCUCGAUGUUGAUGGCAGGACAAAGGGGCGCCUGGACCAUGGGUGAUGUGGUCGAGAAGAGUUUGGAAGGGCCCCUGGCACCUUCUACAGAUGAGCCCUCCCAGAAAACAGGAGACUUGGUCGAGAUCUUAAAUGGGGAAAAGGUCAAAUUUGACGACGCGGGACUCUCCUUAAUUCUUCAGAAUGGCCUGGAAACCCUGCGAAUGGAAAACGCUCUGACAGAUGUCAUCUUGUGUGUGGACAUUCAGGAAUUCUCCUGCCACCGCGUGGUGCUUGCCGCAGCCAGCAACUAUUUCAGGGCCAUGUUCUGCAACGAUUUAAAGGAAAAGUAUGAGAAAAGGAUCAUUAUUAAAGGGGUUGAUGCUGAGACCAUGCACACUCUGUUGGACUACACGUACACCAGCAAGGCGCUGAUCACCAAGCAGAAUGUCCAGCGGGUCCUGGAGGCUGCUAACCUCUUCCAGUUCCUGCGGAUGGUGGAUGCCUGUGCCAGCUUCCUCACUGAAGCCUUGAACCCAGAAAACUGCGUUGGAAUACUGAGGCUGGCUGACACACACUCGCUGGACAGUCUAAAGAAGCAGGUUCAGAGUUACAUCAUUCAAAACUUUGUGCAGAUUCUGAACUCUGAGGAGUUUCUUGACCUGCCCGUGGACACUCUGCACCACAUCUUGAAGAGUGAUGACCUUUACGUGACCGAGGAGGCUCAGGUGUUUGAGACCGUGAUGAGCUGGGUCCGGCACAAGCCAUCAGAACGACUCUGCUUACUCCCCUAUGUCCUCGAGAACGUGCGCUUACCGCUUCUGGACCCGUGGUACUUUGUGGAGACGGUGGAAGCAGAUCCUCUCAUCAGGCAGUGCCCAGAGGUCUUCCCGCUGCUCCAGGAAGCCAGGAUGUACCACCUUUCUGGCAAUGAGGUGGCAAAGAAACACAGCAUGAUGUUUGGAAAUAUAAUUCUUCGAUCAACAAGUGGAUUCAGAUUGAGUAUUUAAACAUAGGCCGCUGGAGGCAUAAGAUGGUGGUGUUGGGUGGCAAGGUCUAUGUGAUCGGAGGCUUUGACGGCUUACAGAGAAUCAACAAUGUGGAGACCUACGACCCCUUUCACAACUGCUGGUCAGAGGUAUAGGACACGAUUUCUACCAGUAACUGCCUGUAUUAUUACUUCAGUGCUUUUUUAAAAAGCUUUGGAACGUGCCUGCCGUGGUGGUCAGCUUUCUGAUCACUUUACUUCCAAGGAGAACAGUUUUGGUGGCUCUGAGCUUCCCUCCUCCUAGGAGCUAUUGCUUCAGUAUUGCUGAUCAAGUCACAGAAACAAUGUCCUUCCAAGUGGUGAAGGUCUGUGUGGGCACCUGUCCUAAUUUGGACAGAACCCCAGAUGUGCACAGAGGCUCACCCUGUCCUUAGAUGGGAGAUCUCUUGGUCUGCAUGUCUUGGUGUAGAGUCUUGUCUCCUCAGAUGCCUUCUCUCCUAUUCUUCUCCACACUGGACACAUGCGGAUCACUUUACUACACCGUUUAUGAACCCAGAGUGAUUUGGUCAUGUUAGAAAUCAUCCCUUCUUUAUUUUCCCAUGGAUGAUGAGCCACUUACAGGCCUGCAUGUCAGACUUUAGUAAUGCAACCUCAGGUAUAUAUCAGACCCAGGAAAAGAAAAGCCACCUCAUCUCAUUUCCAGGUUAUUCCCAGUUUCAAAUUUUCUUUCUCCUUAUCAGAUCAGAUGUCCAAGCAUGUUCCAGCUUAAUGGAAUGUACAACACAGUCAUUGUAGGCACAAGCAAAGGUAGCCAGGUCACCACAUCUAGCCAAGACUGUCAGCCUGAAAAGUGCUAUAUUGAGAGCCCUUAACAUGUAUGGGGGACAUGCCCAGGAUCUUCUCAAAACAAGCCCUAUCACAGAGCUGCUCCACGAUCUAAAAGGAUCCUGUAAAUAAAUGGGCAAGAGGCUCUUGGAAGUCUCCUUUACUGUCCUGGGGUUCACAGGAUAGAAGCACACGUCUGACUUAAUCUCAAAAUCCUCAAUGCUGCCCCAUAAUGGAAGAGUCUGCUUACCUGUGGCCACCGUUUCAGCUUUUCUUCCUAGAUAUAAGCACCAAGGAAAAUCAAUGCUGGUACAUAGUAGGCAUUCCAUAAAUAUUUUUCGAGUGGAUGAGCACAUGAAUGAAUAUGAAUAUGCAUGUAUAAAACAUCAUUUUCCUCCCACACUGGCUGACUUCAUCUGUAUAAACUUAUUCUUGCCUGAGAGCUGGAUUCCGGGAGAGGCUGGCACAUCCCAACACACAGCUUGCUCUAGCUUGCGUGGAGCCUGGAGGGAGGGUGGGAAAUGCAUGCUUUCAUUCUUGCUGUGUCUUAAGAGGAGUCAAGCCCAUGGGCCUUGUGACUAUAGGCAAAAGAUGCCCAGUUCUGUGUCCCGGAGCUCUGUCCUGUAUCCUGGGAGCUACUGCAGCAAUCUGGGCAGCAUGACUGACAGCUUCUUCUUGUGCCCUGUGCCUCUACAGGCCGCACCCCUCCUUGUCCAUGUCAGUUCCUUUGCAGCCACCAGCCAUAAGAAGAAGCUGUAUGUGAUCGGGGGAGGGCCCAAUGGGAAACUGGCCACAGACAAGACUCAGUGUUAUGACCCUUCCACCAACAAGUGGAGUUUGAAGGCGGCCAUGCCCGUGGAGGCUAAAUGCAUCAAUGCAGUGAGUUUCCGGGACCGCAUCUAUGUCGUUGGUGAGUAAUGGCUUCUUAUUGGUCUGAAUGGCUUAGAACCUGAUGAGCGCCUGGCUGCAGCACGUAAACGGUGUGUCGCGGUGUCUCCAGCGCUGGCAACUCACUGCCCCUAGGACCCACUCUGGCUUUCAGGAGAGCCAUCAAUCGACUGUUUCUCUUGGCAAGAGGGUAGACUUGGCCUAAUCAGAAGUUGAAUUUUAGUGGUUAAGAGGGAAGAAACCAGAAAAAUGGAGCGAUGCCCACCGUGUUUCCUCCCUCUCCUCAGGUGGGGCCAUGAGAGCGCUGUACGCCUACAGCCCGCUGGAAGACAGCUGGUGCCUGGUGACCCAGCUCAGCCACGAGCGGGCCAGCUGCGGUAUCGCGCCCUGCAACAACCGGCUCUACAUCACCGGCGGGCGGGACGAGAAGAACGAGGUUAUCGCCACGGUGCUGUGCUGGGACCCCGAGGCCCAGAAACUGACAGAGGAGUGCGUCCUGCCCCGGGGCGUGUCGCACCACGGCAGCGUCACCAUCAGGAAGUCGUACACCCACAUCCGCAGGAUCGUGCCCGGAGCAGUGUCUGUCUGACGGCAGGAUGGGGAGCUGGAGAGCCCCCCCGACCCUCAGCGUACCCGCCUCACCUCUCACCCUCCUCCAGUCCCACUUCAGGCAGCAGGCUCGAGUUUGAGGCCAUACAUCAGGGGAUCCCCUUGACUCACUUUGGGGGAACCUUGGAAGUCACAGUUUGGGGUCACUUGAGACCGGCCAGGAAUGUUUGCAUGACCUACCUCAGGAGGGGAGGCGAGGAAGAGUAAUAUUUAGCAUUCAGGACCCACCCACCCUAUGCCGGCUUCUGUGCCAGGCACUUCCUUUUAUCGGUUCAUUUAACCUGGUGACUGGCUCUUAUCACUUCUAGUUUACAGGUGAGGGAACCAAGUUUCACAGAGGCUAAGUGGCGUGCCCCUGAUCACUCAGAUAGCAAGUAGCUACCCCAGGAGUCUAAAAUCCAGGUCUUUCAUCUCCGAAGUCAAUGCUCUUUCCACCAUGCUGCCUAUCUCAGAGCAGGAAAAACAAACAAAAAACAACAACAAAACCUGGCUCUUGCUGGGCGUGGCGGCUCACGCCUGUAAUCCCAGCCCUAUGGGAGGCUGAGGCGGGCGGAUGACCUGAGGUCAGGAGUUCAAGACCAGCCUGGCCAACAUGGUGAGACCGCCCCGUCUCUACUAAAAAUACAAAAAUUAGCCGCGUGCAGUGGCAGGCGCCUGUAAUUCCAGCUACUCAGGAGGCUGAGGCAGGAGGAUCACUUGAACUUGGGAGGUGGAGGUUGCAGUGAGCCGAGAUCGCCACACUGCACUGCAGCCCGGGAAACAAAAGUGAAGCUCUGUCUUCAAAACAAAAACAAAAACAAAAACAAAAACAAAGAAACCUGGCUCAUUUCUUGUUUCGGCAAGUCUGCUAAAAGAUUCACUCAGCACAGCAGGGAAAUAAAGGUGUUUCCUGCUUUCUUUCCUUUUCUUUCUUAUUCUGCAUCCUCCCUCGUCCCCGCCCUUUACCAAUAUUUAAACCAAGGAGUCAUUUGGGCUCCUUGCCAAGAACAUCUCAUAGGUUCUUCCACUUGAAAGGUCUGGGGGAUGGGCUUGGGAAGGCCUGUUUGCUUUGAAAGAGAUGAAAUACUUGUGUUCUGUCCUCCUCCCAUUGAAACCCUCUUUUUUUUUUUUUUGAGAUGAAGUCGCCCAGGCUGGAGUGCAGUGGCAUGAUCUCGGCUCACUGCAACCUCUGUCACCCUGGUUCAAGUGAUUUUCCUGCCUCAGCCUCCUGAGUAGCUGGGAUUACAGGCACCUGCCACCGCGCCUGGCUAAUUUUUGUAGUUUUAGUAGAGACGGGGUUUCACCAUCUUGGCCAGGCUGGUCUUGAACGCCUGACCUUGUGAUCUGCCCGCCUCGGCCUCCCGAAGUGCUGGGAUUACAGGUGUGAGCCACUGGGCCCGGUCUUUUUUUUUUUAAAUGAUCAUAAGAUGGCCCAUUUUGGACCGGAACUGUCAUUGCCAGACAGAAUUGUACCUUUAGCACAUUCUGGUGCCCUGGCCUCUUAGUGUUCACCAGUUGUACUGCAAUAUAGACAAGAUGUCUCUAGAGACUCAAACUACUGUUUUAUUAAAAAAGUAAACACCUGAGCACAGCUGGCCUACACAGGAGCGACAGAUUCUCCUUGAUGGUACACUUUCUAGUUUUUACACAGUGAUUUAGGUCCACGUUCCUGAUACCCCAUCCUCCUGAAGCCUUCGUUUUCAAGACUUUUAAAAAGCACUUCUACUUGGUUUUUUGAUCAGUGUAGCUCAAUUGUGACUUAAAGAACAGAAUCUGUCCUUCACUGUAAGAGCUACAGCUUUCAAAUGAGCUCACUGGAAAUUCAUUCUAAUCCCCAAGCUGGAGAAACAGGUUAAGAGAUCCUGUUUCAUAUGCUGUAUUUAAAAAGCAACAAUGAUAACAACAUAGUAACUGCGUUACCCAAUGGACUUUAUUUUCAUCAUAUGAUUUCAAUUCUCUUUAUAGAGUUUUAUUUCAUAUCCGGUGUGGCUUGUUCUUUUCAGCAGUUUGGGAAGUUAGUUAUUAGAGUUGAUAGUGAAUUGAAUUUUCAUUAAACAGUCACGGUUAGAAGAAGCUAAUAUUUGAAACAGAUUUUAAAAACUUGAAAAAUUACAGGUGAGAUUUCUGUUUAUGCCAGAUUAUUGAAGAUAAAUAUAAAUGUAUGUUGGUGUGUGAAAUGCUCUGUGCCUUAGAAGCGUGACAGUUCAGCUCUCUGCUGUGGAAAGUAACACAGGGCAAUAGAAACAUAUUUGUGGAAUUUUAGAACAAACUAUUGCUGACUCAUGAGCACUAUAAUAACCAUCAGGAAGCUCCCAACUGAAGCAAUGUAACAGUGUAAUCUAGUUCAAUUCAGCAAACAUUCAUGGAGUUCUUCAUGUCUGUCAAGCCUUGAGGACACCCACGAAUGGCAAAUCUCCACGCUAGACACUCAAUACAGGUAAAUAGGCCACCAGUUAAUAUUCUUGUUUUUAUUUUCUUCAAGUUAGCUAAAAAUGAGAUGCGUAUGAAGUGAGGAGGCUGGAUCCAAGUCUUGAUUGCCUUUCAGGGGGUCAAGGUGGUAAGCUGUGCAGUGAAGUCAACCAGUGGCCAUGGCUUACAUGUUUGUCUCUUUGAGAUCGCCACCAGAACCAUUUGUGAACUGAUUUGUGAAGGAAAAGUCAGUCUUACUCCAAAGACUAUUGCAGGGAGGAACUUCCAGAGAGGAAAUCCAAUGACAAUGGUACUGGCAUACACAGGGAGCCUCCCUUCAAAAAGACAGCGCCCCUAGUCAGGGAGGGGAUGGCGGUCCUUUGAUAAGACCCAUAGGCAAACUUCGAGCCCAUCAGCAGGUCAACCCUAUGCUGGGAAAGUGAGGAUUUGGGAUUUCUGUGCUAUAAACCUGAUUCUAAAUGUAGGACCCAAGUUUCUGGACUACUUCAGAAUACCUAAAUGAAUCAUGGAAACACUCUUUAUGAUUUUUUACAACACCAGAUAUGCAGGUGAAUUGUGGAAAAUGUCAUGUAGCUGACACUCAAGAAAUAGGGAUUCCUAAUAAUGGCAUGGGUAGGGAACAGAUACACCUGGUUAGAAGGUCUAGGGUUCUGUAUAUGAAGCUGCCAGUCUGUAGCUCUUCGAGAAAGAAAGUUCAAGUCAUUUGGGGGAAACUUAAGAAUAGUCAUCAGGGUUUUAGCUUCUAGGCACCAGCCAAGGAUGAGAACUUCUAAAAUCUAAAAUCCAUUUCAAGAAAUAAAGACGAACACAUUUGCAGGAAGGUAACUGUUAUAACCCACACCAUCAGCAGGGGGAAAGCCAAGCUGAGAAUAAACCCAGAGACAAAGAACCCUCGGACUCAGGCAGGACAUGGCAGGAUGUUCUGGCACAGCAGACUGGAGACUGAGGCAGGGCCUGUGAGUGGACAGAGCACCCCUGGCUGGGAAGAAGAAGAUGGGGUAGGAGGAGGUCAGGUUCCAAGGAUGCAGGUCUGGAAAAUGAUAUCGGAGGCCCUGGAGUUUGUGAGCUUGGCUCUAGUCCCAAGAAGGGUGAGGGAGAAUAAGGGUAAGGGAGUAUUCUAGGCAAGGAACUAAGGAAGGAAUCCCCUUCUUAGAGCAGAGGCACAAGUUAGAGCAGGCCCAGCAUUUGGGCCAACUUACUGUGGGGCCUCUGAGCUGCUCAGCUGGGUCUCCUGUCCUAGAGGGAAGGUGGCCCAGAGUCUUUGGUGGAGCGGAAUCUGUAGAUGAGGUUAAGGGACUCCAGUUGCCAAGGUUGAUCUGAAACAGGCAGGGAGCUAAGCUCAUCAGAACACCAACAGAUUCAUGUUCUCGUCUUAGCUUUCAUCUAUUCUGGUCUCAAUGGCUUCGGGAAACACACAUAUACACAUACACCAUGCCCUUGAACUCAAAGCAAACUACGCUCUCAGGGAAAUACAAAUAUCACGUUCUUAUAGCUGUAAAGUAUAGCUUAGCUAUUUAUAGAAGACUAUGAGGUACUGUUGUGAGUUAUUUGCUUAUCCUGUUUUAUUCUGAAAAAUGAAAGUGCUCAAUAGAAUUUUUAACGUUGGCAACACCAUAAGGAUUUCUUAUGUUAAGUCCCAACUUGGGGUUGCAAAAUCAUUUUUUCCCUUAAUACCUGGGUGUUGUAUUAGAUCUCAUAAUUUGACAAGUUAACCUUUUAGAAAUCCACAUAUAUCUCAAAUCUGGCUACUGCAAAACCAGUUUUGACAGGUCAGAUUUUCAUAUGUAUAGGUAUAAAUAGCCAACACUCAGUGAACAAAAUCCUUUAAGCAUUUUGGUUACAUAAAGUUGUAUGUUUUAAGUGAUCAAACUAAGAAUAUUGUUUAUAGGUUUUAAAAACCAAACCAAUAAAAUUUUUAUUUAUUCAAUAAAAUAUGCACAGAACAGA